AGAUCCCCGGAGGAGUUGUUGCUGGGCGGAGUCAGAGCAGUUCUUGAGGUUCAAGGAGGCGGGGGAGACCUGAGCUCACGCUUGCUGAGACAGAAGUCACAGCAGGAUUAUGCCCCUCAGGGCAAGAGGAAGAGUUCAGAAACUGCCGCCGUAACCCAAGAACAAAGUUGCAUGCAGAGCCAACCUAAGAGCUUCAAAAUCGGGAUUCCUUACUGAGAAAGAUGUAUAACAUAAAACAGUCAACAGAUACCAAGGAAGCAGCAGCCAUCGAGGCUAGAAGAAAUCGAGAAAAAGAGCGACAAAACCGAUUCUUCAAUGUGCGGAACCGAGUCAUGGGGGUGGAUGUCCAGGCCCUGAACAACCAGGUGGGAGACCGAAAGCGUCGGGAAGCAGCAGAAAGAAGCAAGGAGGCAGCUUAUGGUACCAGCCAGGUGCAGUAUGAUGUGGUAGUCCAGAUGUUAGAGAAGGAAGAGGCAGAUCGAACACGUCAGCUGGCCAAGAAAGUCCAGGAGUUUCGGGAGCAGAAGCAGCAGCUCAAGAACGGGCGUGAAUUUAGUCUUUGGGAUCCAGGCCAAGUCUGGAAGGGGCUUCCAACCUAUCUUAGUUACAGUAAUACCUAUCCUGGUCCAGCCAGCCUGCAGUACUUCUCUGGGGAAGACCUAGACAGGGACACACGGCUGAGAAUGCAGCAGGGGCAGUUCAGGUACAACUUGGAAAGGCAACAGCAGGAGCAACAGCAAGCCAAGGUUGAUGAGAAUUAUACAGGUAAGCAGCCCGGCCCUCCAGACUCAGAGACCUGAGGCCUAGUGGGGAUCUGUCCUAAGCUGAGUACAGCAGCCAGGGGACCAGAACUGUGUGGGGAGGUCCACUUAUCCAUAGGGUUGGUGCUGAAAUGUUAGGUUGUGCAGACCCCAACCUCCCUGACUUCCUUCAGUAACUGACAGUGUAGCAUUGUUCUUGAUUAGUUUGGCACUCCAUUACGUGGAGGCAGCACAGUGCAGACAGACCUAAUGGCUCUGCCACUUACUAGCUGGUUUGGGCAAAUGAAUUUUCCCUUCUGUGCUUCAGUUUCUUCAUCUUUAAAAUGAGAAUAAUAAUUUAUACCACAUAGAGUAGCUACUAUUAUGAUAUUGUCUGUGGCCACAUCCUUCUCUUCCAUUAGAAGAAGCCCUUCAAGGGCAAGGACCAUGUCUUAUCUACUUGCACUGUUCACCCUUCACAUCAACCCUGUUACAGCACUCUGUUCUGCUGGACCACUUAUUGUAGUUGUAGCUAAUUGUGAAAGUAUUUGUUUAAUAUCUGUCUUCUCCCUAAAAUGUCAGCCUACUGAAGAUGAACCAUCUCUUUCAUGUCUACCCAUCUCCCAGUUGCAUAGUACAGUGUCUGACAGGUCUUAGGAACAGCAAGGAGCUCAGUGUGGCUGGAGCAGAAAAAAAUUGUCAGUACCUUUGCUCAUGCCAUGCCCUCAGCCUGGAAUGCCCUUUGCUCUUUUAGCCUGUAUACAAAAUGUAUUUCAAGGAUCACCUCUUCCUGGAAGCCUUCCUCUUUUCCACCAUCCAAAACCCUCUUAAUACCCUGUGUACAUCCCUGCCAUUGCUCUUGCCAGAUUGUGGUCUAUGUUUGAUCUGUGUCCCCAACUAGACAGGGAGUUCUCUGAGGACAGGAUUUAAUUCGAUGGUAUCAUUAGAACCCAGCACAUGGCCCUUAGACUGAGAUUCAGAGAUAUGAAAUGAUUUACCCAAAAUCACACAGCUCAGAAGCAGCAGAACUGACAUUGGGACCCAGGUCCAUUGGAGGCAUCUUUUAGUUAUGCGCUUGAGAAAUCGUUGUUGCUGCACCUAGUUCCUUCCACAUCCCUACAACUCGGACACUAACCCCCUCCUAAACAUUCGUACACACACAAACACAAAACUUGCUGAACAAAUGGCUGGAUGAGUGAAACAGGAAUGGAGCAAGCCAGUACAGU